CAUGGGGCUUUUUGUUUUUAUAUUCUUUUUUUCCUUUGAAGCCUUGACUGUGGUGUGUUGUGUAUAGUUGAUUGGCUUUUUUUCUGGCUGCUUUCAGAGUGCUGAGGCUGUGUUUGGGUUUCUUUGUUGUAGAUUGCUUCCUGCAUUGGGUUUUACAGGCUUUUGGGUGCUGAAGGAAUUUUUGUUUGUUCAUAUAAUUCAGGCUCUAGUCCAAUAGAUGGUGCAUAAGAGUAAGGGCCAGCAGAUGGUCUCUUACAUACUUCUUUUAUAUCUUGAUGCAUAUGUAGCAGUGCUCUGGGGAAGGGGAGAUGGGAGGGUGAGAGAUACCUGCCCCCACCCACCCUCCAAGUCCAUUCCAGGGCUUUGGUGGAGCCUUUUCCAAUCGUUGGCAUUGUUCCUGCAUUUCCUUAGUCCCAUGGGGGACCUUGUUGGGCUGCAUUCUCCCCUCCUUUAGGGGUGGCCUGAGCCAAAGGUUAGAUUGCCAGGAAACCUGUAACUCCCCAGGAACCUGCUGGUCCUCUGAGCUUGGCAGGGUCAGAGUGGGCUGUGGGAUAUGUCUGUGAGUGGUCUGAUGAUACAGGGGUCAAAGGCACAUGAUCCUGGGCAGGGCAGUGGUGCCAUAGAUGUGAAAUUGGUAUGGUGCCCACAGCCCAGGGAUUUUAGUCCAGCUGAUGACUGUGGGGUCCACCUAGUUCAUGCUUUUCAGACUGGGUCUCCUUCUAGUGUCUUCCCUAGGAGCAGGCCCGCCCAGCUAGAUUUGUACCAAGCCUUCUUGUGCUCAUAUAACUGGGCUCUUCCACGUGUUCAGGGCUGUAUGGUUUCCUUGGGCAGAAGCUGUGGCUGGCCAACAGCUACACCCUUCCUGGACCAGUCUUGCAAAGGGAGGGAUGCCUGGCUCCUACACUGGCACACAAACCAGCACCUCACUCUUCUUUGUGUCCCAAGAGUGGUGGCUCCUCCUCUGCCCAAGCUCUGGCCACAGACCUUAGCUCAAUACCCCUCAGGGUAGUGUGCUCGAAUCCUAGAAAGUUGGGACUUAGCCCACAGCUUUGUCCUCUGGACCCUCAGGACUGAGUACUGGCUGUGCUGAGGAGUCCGAACUGCUCUCAGGCUAUUGGCAAAACAUCCGGGUGGGGCAGUGGAGGCUGAGCUGUGUACACCCUCCUGCGGGAGCAGCCAGGUAGGCAGUUUUGGGAGGGGUUGGCAGACAAGGGGGCACAGAGAUCAGAUGCACCUUAGUACCAUGGGAGAGGUAGCCCUGCUCUCUGCUGGCUGGCAGUCAGCAGGGGCUGCAGCCAGUCAGCAACAUGGAGAGUCUUGGAAGAGGGAUAGUUGUGGUUCCGUUUUGCUGUAGCUGCCCCUUGUAAGCUUCUGGGCUCCGCACAAGACCAAGCUCUUCCUCUACCUACUCUCCAGGCAGAUCCCCUUGCCAAUGCAAAUGUCUGUGGGGGUUGUGGUAUCUCUUGUGGCCAGAAUCACAGAAGUCUGUGGUGGAACUGUGGGUUUUUUGGAGUUCCUUUACUCAUCCCUUCCAAAGGACCUGUUCAGGACCAGCAACCUGUCCUGGUGCUCAGUGACUCUGUGUGGGGCUUCCCACUUCCUCCUUCUUCAGCUUCAGUGUCUGCAUCACCUCUCUAUUGACUUUAGCUGUUUUCUGUCAAAAGAUCUGUUCGAAAUGUAAUCGUUUACUUGAUAUUUUGGUUUCUCUCUGUGGGACAGGCACCUCCCCACUAUGCCUAGUUAGCCAUCUUGUCCCUUCCCAAUCUUAUUUUAAAAUUAUACAAAAAUAAUAUAAUAACUUCCUUAUUUCUGACCUCAUAGCGUGUGAUAAAUAGGUCUCUUCAUUCUUCAUUUAAUGUCGCUAUCAAGGAUAAUUAUGAAUUGUUUUUCAAAAUUAGUGAAAUAGAUUCUUAUGGUACCACUUUAAUAAGAAAUGACUAAAAUGUUCUUAUUCCAAAGAAAUAAGUCUGUCAUCUAAUGGGUGUAUUAAUUAGCUUGAGUCACUCAUUCCACAGUGUGUACACAUAUCAAAAUACCAUGUUGUAUACCAUAAAUACAUAUAAUCUGUGUCAAUUAAGAAAUAAAACGUUAAAGAAAUCACUAAAGUUUACUAAGUUGCUGUAAAUGUUAUUUUAACACAUUGUUUCCACUUCUUUCCAUUGAGUGAAGCUCCUCUAGUUGUCCAAAGUCAGCUUCAAAUACAUAUACUCAUCUAAAAAACUGAAAAAAGGUUUUAGGGAAUGUCCUUCUAACCAGCCUGUUUCCCGGAGGCAAGAUUAGAAAUAUGACUUUGAUGGUAACCAUCCUUUGAUACAGAAAUGGAAACAAUCUCUCAACUUGGUACUCCAGGUUUGAACUUUAAGACAACCAAGUUUCAUAUUCAGUCCACAAUUAGCUCUUGCCCUCACCGUCUGCACGCUAUAGUUCCAUCUUUAUACUCAUACUAUAAUCAGCAUCUACUGUUUGCAGCCCUUGAGUAUACCCAUUAACCUGAAUUAUUUUGAGGGGAGACCCCUCUCUUAUACAUGUCUGCAUCCUCCACAUAACCCAACAUAGUAGAUGUCCAGUAUAUUUUUGUUGGUUAUUUUCUUCUUUAACUUUUGUAUACAUUAUCACAAUAAAGUCCUUCUAACAAGUUUUGUCUCUGUUAUCAUUCCUUGUACUUUUCUUCCCUCCUCUCUUCUCUCAGAGUAAGAGGGUAGAAAUCAAAGUCAGCAGCUCUUACUCUCAGAGUGAGGUUCUUUCUAUUGUUCUAUGUCUCUCUUGCUUUUUCAAUUGUUUCCUUAUAUCUCUCAUUUUCUACAAGCAUACUUUUCUCUUUCCCACCUUAAAACAAUCAUAAAAACUUUUCUUUGAAUCUCUAACCCCUUGACUUAACACUUUUUCUCACCCUUCUCAUUAACAACCUUCUAUAGAAGCUAGCCUUCAUUUCCCACCACUUGUCCAUCAUUUCCUGGGCCUUCUUUAGCUUGGCAUCUGCCCUGUGGCUCCACUGAAACUCCUUUCUUUAAACAUCACUCUUACUUUCUAAUUCCCAAACCAAACUCUCUAAAGCCACCCUCCUUCAAACUCUCCUCUCUGGCCAUCUUGCUUUUACUCCUGUCUCUAUUAGCCAGUCAGCCUCCUGUUGCAUAUUUCUAUCUCCUAGAAAUAUCCAUUGUGUUUUUCACCAGGAUCUUAAGUAUAUAGAAACAUAAACUCAUCAUUUUCUUUCCCUUUUUUCAAACCAGUUUUGCCUCUUGACUUCUAUAUUUUUGGUAAGAAAACUACCAUUCAUUUAGUGAACUUAGCACCAAACCUCAGUACCAUCUGACAGUUUUCUCUCCUUCUCUGUGGAUAUCAUUAAGUCCUAAUAGUUUUACCUGUGUCAUUCGUGCCUUCAUUUUUAUUCUUACUUUCUCUACUCUGGCUUUGCCUCUCAUUAACUUGAACUACUGCUACCAAGAUUGUAUAAGUUGUUUUGUUUCUAUUUUUCUCCAUUUUUGACACACUUGGAACAUCCUAAAAAACUUUUAGUCUUAUUUUUAUAAAGGAAAAGUUGUAUUCGUCUCUGAGCUGAAUAUUUCAGUCUUUCCUCAUGUUCUAACAAAUAUAUUUUAAACUCCUCGGUAUGGUAAUCAGAUUGUUCUAGUCUUCACUUUCCUUUGCUAUGAUAUCUAGUCUGUAUCCUGUGUUCUAGUUCCUUCUCUGUUAUGAUUGUCUCAGGUUUGAUCCCAACUGUCUCUUGGUUCACCUCAACUAUGGAGGACUUUUUCUAUAAGAAGUUACUCUAAUUUAAAAAGAUAUUUUAAUAAUUAAAAUUAUCUUUAUCAAAGGAUAAAUUGUGCUUAAGUUAGUAUGUUACUAAACAUGGGACUGUGCAUAAAGAGAGCUUUAAAAUUCCCACAGCUGCUCCUCUACCUCCAAGGUUCUCAGCAUAGACAGCGGCUUUUUAUGGCCAAAUAGAGGAAUGCCUGUUAGGCAUAUUUAUGCUGCAUCCUUUUUGCACAUCCUGAAUUCAUCCAGGAGAAGAAAAAUGAUGUGCUUCAAUUGAAGUGGACCUAUCGUUUUCUCUUGGCAGCCAAAGGAGGAGCAAAAAGUCCAGAUUGUGUCCUUUAUCUUGUAGGGAUUGCGAUGGUGAGGAGAUAUGAGGAAGAGGGGUAAUAGCAUCAGUUAUCCCAGGGAAAGCAGUCCGUUUACUUGGGCUGGCAUGUUUUCUCUUCAGAUACUUAUACAAUUUACUUCCUCACCACCUCAUCAAGUCUUUGUUCAGAUGAUCCCCUUCUCAAUGAGGCCUGCCUUAAUGACAUCUAAAAUUGCAACCUAUUUUCCCUGGGCACUCCUAACCCCCUUUGCCCUGCUCAAGUUUUUCCUCCCAUAGUGCUCCCCACCUCCUGACAUUCUUCAUGGUUUACUUGUUUAUUAUGAUCAUCGUCUGCUGUCUUUACUAGUAUUUAAGCUCUAUGAGGGCAGGUCUCAUUGACUAUUUCGUUAUUACAAUAUACCCAGAAUGAUGCUGUAGUAGUAGGUGUUAGUAAGUGCUUAGUAAUUAUAUGUUGAAUUAAGUAACAAAAUAACUUACUCAAAAAAUAAUUUUUGUCAUGCCCUAUAUAUGCUAAGAGCUGUGCUGGUGAUGGGGACCUAUAGUGGAAAACAAAUAGAUUUGGUCCUUACCCCCUAUCUUGCUAUCUAGCCAAGAAAGCCUACACCAACAUUACAAUAAAAUGAGAUGAGUGUUUUGUUCCAGGAACACUGUGCUACACAAGGGAUCUCAUGUAGGAGGUCACUGAAGACUUCCCUGAACAAAUGACCAAGCUGAGACUUGAGGAUGGUUAGGAGUUGGCCAAGUAAAGAAUGACAGAAGGAGGAUGCCUCUUCCAGGCAUACUUUAAAGCAUUACUGGUUGAAGGAAUUGUAAUAAGUCAAGUGGCUGGACUAUAGAAAGAGGAAGGCAGGCUGGCCCUGCAAAAAGAGAGGCAGGGAAGAGGUUGAGAGGCCUUUCUAACUCCUUCUAUGGAAUUUUCACUUUUCCCAAAGGCCCGUGGAUUCUCCGUAUACUCUGCAUUACCCCAUGUAAUAAAAUGCUUUUCAGAAUAUGAACAUCUUCCAGUUGACUUUGUUCUCCAUUAGACUGGAUAAAUACUUUGUAAAGAAAUAUGCACUUGGUCAAAGUAACUCUAGGUAUAAUAUCACAUCUUUAUUUUUAGCAUUUGUGGCUGUGGAGCAGGCACAAUUCUGGCCAUGGUAUGUUUGGUUUGGCAUUAGCUAAUACCUUGUUGUUUAAGUAAUACUCAGAUCUUGCUGAAAACAGCAUAGCACAUUUUAGCGUUAAUCUCCAGAGUAAUCAGAUCAGUGACACAUACUGGGGAAGCAAAGAAAAUAGGCUUAGGAGGUAUCAGAUAUCUUCGUUUGGUAAAGACCUACAUUGAUAUGGGUUUCCUCUAAUUAUGUGUUAAGAUUCUCCUGCUUUCAGUAUAUAGGCCAAAGUUCAGACCACAUUAUUGAGAUAGGUAGAAAUUUGCUUUAAACUUCCUCUUAAUACUCUCCCUUUCAUCAUCUCUUCUUUUAGAGUUUCCUUAUGGACACAGUAGUGUCCUGCUAUUUUCUGGUUGCCUAGAGGAACACCCUACCCUCACUAUUACAUGGUAUUAUUGGAUGUGCAUCUAACCAAUCUGUGCUUUCUGCCACUAACAAACUCAAAACUCACUUCUCUUUUGUCCCCUCCCUUUUGGGGCUUCCUAGGUGAUGUGUCGUCUAAUCUCUUGUAAUGCUAAUUCAUGCUGAUAUCUUUAUGACUACAACAUCUCUUGGAAGUAUUUGCAUUUUAAAUGAUGAACUAUGCAUUAAAUCAGUUUGCACUCAUGAAACUUCAAGCUUCAGGGAAAAAAACUUCAAGCUAGAGCUGGGAAAAUCAUGUUGCUAAGGGAAAAAUAAGAAUACAAGGUGGGACUUGUAGUCCCUUUAAUUUGAUCCUUGCAUGUCGUAUAUUUGGUCAGUUUCUAAGGCCUGUCAGUUUUCACAGAUAAAAGAUCACAAAAGCUUUACUCUCUUCUGAGUGUCUGUGGUCCCCUACACAAAUUUGCAGGACUACUUAGUACUUUAGAGCACAAACAUCAGUCUGGAGGUAGAGAUGGAGCCCUUACUCAUGAUAGUCACAAAAGUUGAUCUAUUGCUUAACUUCUUAGAGACUUGCUUAUAUUUUUUCCCCUUUUUCUAAAAUACACUUCUUUCUGUAGUAUAUUAAAUAAGUGUUAAUGAUUGUCAAAGUAUUUCAAAACUAUGAAAUGUGUAUAUAUAGGAGAUAGUAAUUAAAUGCUUCCUUUUAGAGUUCUAAAGAUGUUUUUUGUAUAAGAUUUCAGAUAGCUCCUCUGAAGAAUUCCAGCCUAUUGGAACCCAAAUCCUGAUGCAUAUAAUAAAGUUUAAAAGGCUUAUUUUUUAUGUAUGUAACAAGAACUCACCUUUAUAACUUCUUACGUGAGUGAAGUAAAAUUGUUCCAUAUAAGAGAAAUGCAUCCUCUCCAAAUACAGCGUGCAGAAAUAGCAUCUGAAGAUUUAUUACAGAAACAAAACAAAUGGUGCGCAAUUAAAAUAGGCAUGUUCUCCAGGAAAAACAUCCCCAGCAGGCUUCAAAAUCCUGACUCUACUUUUGGAUUUGUCUGGUCUGGUCUGGCAUAUAUACCAAGAAUCUAAAGUAUUUUAGGGUGAUGCAAUUUUUUAUUUCAGUGAUCGUGAUGAUACGAGAAAUCAAAGAGCACUUGGGAAAGUGUGAUUCAAAGCUGGGACCAACAAGAUGCAGUAUCCAUGGAUGUCACUGACCUGGCUUCCCGCCAUUAUGGCCACCAAUUAUGUGUGUCUUUCACUGAAGCGUCAACCACACCUCUGCCAUCAGGUAUGCGGAGACCAAAGCCAAGGGGCUGUUUUCCUGCGGGAAUUUACACUGAUUCGAAGAGAGAGCCUCCAUGAAGAUUUCCUGUCUGACCUCUUGAAUAGUCACAAAACUGAAGACUCGAGUUCCAGGACCGCACGCUCCGAGGAGGACCGGGACGGCCUAUGGGAUGCCUGGGGCCCAUGGAGUGAAUGCUCACGCACCUGCGGGGGUGGGGCCUCCUACUCUCUGAGGCGCUGCCUGAGCAGCAAGAGCUGUGAAGGAAGAAAUAUCCGAUACAGAACAUGCAGUAAUGUGGACUGCCCACCAGAAGCAGGUGAUUUCCGAGCUCAGCAAUGCUCAGCUCAUAAUGAUGUCAAGCACCAUGGCCAGUUUUAUGAAUGGCUUCCUGUGUCUAAUGACCCUGACAACCCAUGUUCACUCAAGUGCCAAGCCAAAGGAACAACCCUGGUUGUUGAACUAGCACCUAAGGUCUUAGAUGGUACGCGUUGCUAUACAGAAUCUUUGGAUAUGUGCAUCAGUGGUUUAUGCCAAAUUGUUGGCUGCGAUCACCAGCUGGGAAGCACCGUCAAGGAAGAUAACUGUGGGGUCUGCAACGGAGAUGGGUCCACCUGCCGGCUGGUCCGAGGGCAGUAUAAAUCCCAGCUCUCCGCAACCAAAUCGGAUGAUACUGUGGUUGCAAUUCCCUAUGGAAGUAGACAUAUUCGCCUUGUCUUAAAAGGUCCUGAUCACUUAUAUCUGGAAACCAAAACCCUCCAGGGGACUAAAGGUGAAAACAGUCUCAGCUCCACAGGAACUUUCCUUGUGGACAAUUCUAGUGUGGACUUCCAGAAAUUUCCAGACAAAGAGAUACUGAGAAUGGCUGGACCACUCACAGCAGAUUUCAUUGUCAAGAUUCGUAACUCGGGCUCCGCUGACAGUACAGUCCAGUUCAUCUUCUAUCAACCCAUCAUCCACCGAUGGAGGGAGACGGAUUUCUUUCCUUGCUCAGCAACCUGUGGAGGAGGUUAUCAGCUGACAUCGGCUGAGUGCUACGAUCUGAGGAGCAACCGUGUGGUUGCUGACCAAUACUGUCACUAUUACCCAGAGAACAUCAAACCCAAACCCAAGCUUCAGGAGUGCAACUUGGAUCCUUGUCCAGCCAGUGACGGAUACAAGCAGAUCAUGCCUUAUGACCUCUACCAUCCCCUUCCUCGGUGGGAGGCCACCCCAUGGACCGCGUGCUCCUCCUCGUGUGGGGGGGGCAUCCAGAGCCGGGCAGUUUCCUGUGUGGAGGAGGACAUCCAGGGGCAUGUCACUUCAGUGGAAGAGUGGAAAUGCAUGUACACCCCUAAGAUGCCCAUCGCGCAGCCCUGCAACAUUUUUGACUGCCCUAAAUGGCUGGCACAGGAGUGGUCUCCGUGCACAGUGACAUGUGGCCAGGGCCUCAGAUACCGUGUGGUCCUCUGCAUCGACCAUCGAGGAAUGCACACAGGAGGCUGUAGCCCAAAAACAAAGCCCCACAUAAAAGAGGAAUGCAUCGUACCCACUCCCUGCUAUAAACCCAAAGAGAAACUUCCAGUCGAGGCCAAGUUGCCAUGGUUCAAACAAGCUCAAGAGCUAGAAGAAGGAGCUGCUGUGUCAGAGGAGCCCUCGUUCAUCCCAGAGGCCUGGUCGGCCUGCACAGUCACCUGUGGUGUGGGGACCCAGGUGCGAAUAGUCAGGUGCCAGGUGCUCCUGUCUUUCUCUCAGUCCGUGGCUGACCUGCCUAUUGACGAGUGUGAAGGGCCCAAGCCAGCAUCCCAGCGUGCCUGUUAUGCAGGCCCAUGCAGCGGGGAAAUUCCUGAGUUCAACCCAGACGAGACAGAUGGGCUCUUUGGUGGCCUGCAGGAUUUCGACGAGCUGUAUGACUGGGAGUAUGAGGGGUUCACCAAGUGCUCCGAGUCCUGUGGAGGAGGUGUCCAGGAGGCUGUGGUGAGCUGCUUGAACAAACAGACUCGGGAGCCUGCUGAGGAGAACCUGUGCGUGACCAGCCGCCGGCCCCCACAGCUCCUGAAGUCCUGCAAUUUGGAUCCCUGCCCAGCAAGGUGGGAAAUUGGCAAGUGGAGUCCAUGUAGUCUCACAUGUGGGGUCGGCCUACAGACCAGAGACGUCUUCUGCAGCCACCUGCUUUCCAGAGAGAUGAAUGAAACAGUCAUCCUGGCUGAUGAGCUGUGUCGCCAGCCCAAGCCCAGCACGGUGCAAGCUUGUAACCGCUUUAAUUGCCCCCCAGCCUGGUACCCUGCACAGUGGCAGCCGUGUUCCAGAACGUGUGGCGGGGGUGUUCAGAAACGUGAGGUUCUUUGCAAGCAGCGCAUGGCUGAUGGCAGCUUCCUGGAGCUUCCUGAGACCUUCUGUUCAGCUUCAAAACCUGCCUGCCAGCAAGCAUGCAAGAAAGAUGACUGUCCCAGCGAGUGGCUUCUCUCAGACUGGACAGAGUGUUCCACAAGCUGCGGGGAAGGCACCCAGACUCGAAGCGCCAUUUGCCGAAAGAUGCUGAAAACCGGCCUCUCAACGGUUGUCAAUUCCACCCUGUGCCCGCCCCUGCCUUUCUCUUCCUCCAUCAGGCCCUGUAUGCUGGCAACCUGUGCAAGGCCCGGGCGGCCAUCCACGAAGCACAGCCCGCACAUCGCGGCCGCCAGGAAGGUCUACAUACAGACUCGCAGGCAGAGGAAGCUGCACUUCGUGGUGGGGGGCUUCGCCUACCUGCUCCCCAAGACGGCGGUGGUGCUGCGCUGCCCGGCGCGCAGGGUCCGCAAGCCCCUCAUCACCUGGGAGAAGGACGGCCAGCACCUCAUCAGCUCGACGCACGUCACGGUGGCCCCCUUCGGCUAUCUCAAGAUCCACCGCCUCAAGCCCUCGGAUGCAGGCGUCUACACCUGCUCAGCGGGCCCGGCCCGGGAGCACUUUGUGAUUAAGCUCAUCGGAGGCAACCGCAAGCUCGUGGCCCGGCCCUUGAGCCCGAGAAGUGAGGAAGAGGUGCUUGCGGGGAGGAAGGGCGGCCCGAAGGAGGCCCUGCAGACCCACAAACACCAGAACGGGAUCUUCUCCAACGGCAGCAAGGCGGAGAAGCGGGGCCUGGCCGCCAACCCGGGGAGCCGCUACGACGACCUCGUCUCCCGGCUGCUGGAGCAGGGCGGCUGGCCCGGAGAGCUGCUGGCCUCGUGGGAGGCGCAGGACUCUGCGGAAAGGAACACGACCUCGGAGGAGGACCCGGGUGCAGAGCAAGUGCUCCUGCACCUGCCCUUCACCAUGGUGACCGAGCAGCGGCGCCUGGACGACAUCCUGGGGAACCUCUCCCAGCAGCCCGAGGAGCUGCGCGACCUCUACAGCAAGCACCUGGUGGCCCAGCUGGCCCAGGAGAUCUUCCGCAGCCACCUGGAGCACCAGGACACGCUCCUGAAGCCCUCGGAGCGCAGGACUUCCCCAGUGACUCUCUCGCCUCAUAAACACGUGUCUGGCUUCAGCAGCUCCCUGCGGACCUCCUCCACCGGGGACGCCGGGGGAGGCUCUCGAAGGCCACACCGCAAGCCCACCAUCCUGCGCAAGAUCUCAGCGGCCCAGCAGCUCUCAGCCUCGGAGGUGGUCACCCACCUGGGGCAGACGGUGGCCCUGGCCAGCGGGACACUGAGUGUUCUUCUGCACUGUGAGGCCAUCGGCCACCCAAGGCCUACCAUCAGCUGGGCCAGGAAUGGAGAAGAAGUUCAGUUCAGUGACAGGAUUCUUCUACAGCCAGAUGAUUCCUUACAGAUCUUGGCACCAGUGGAAGCAGAUGUGGGUUUCUACACUUGCAAUGCCACCAAUGCCUUGGGAUACGACUCUGUCUCCAUUGCCGUCACAUUAGCAGGAAAGCCACUAGUGAAAACGUCACGAAUGACAGUGAUCAACACGGAGAAGCCUGCAGUCACAGUCGAUAUAGGAAGCACCAUCAAAACAGUGCAGGGAGUGAAUGUGACAAUCAACUGCCAGGUUGCAGGAGUGCCUGAAGCUGAAGUCACUUGGUUCAGGAAUAAAAGCAAACUGGGCUCCCCGCACCAUCUGCACGAAGGCUCCUUGCUGCUCACAAACGUGUCCUCCUCGGAUCAGGGCCUGUACUCCUGCAGGGCGGCCAAUCUUCAUGGAGAGCUGACUGAGAGCACCCAGCUGCUGAUCCUAGAUCCCCCCCAAGUCCCCACACAGUUGGAAGACAUCAGGGCCUUGCUCGCUGCCACUGGACCGAACCUUCCUUCAGUGCUGACGUCUCCUCUGGGAACACAGCUGGUCCUGGAUCCUGGGAAUUCUGCUCUCCUUGGCUGCCCCAUCAAAGGUCACCCUGUCCCUAAUAUCACCUGGUUUCAUGGUGGUCAGCCAAUUGUCACUGCCACAGGACUGACGCAUCACAUCUUGGCAGCUGGACAGAUCCUUCAAGUUGCAAACCUUAGCGGUGGGUCUCAAGGGGAAUUCAGCUGCCUUGCUCAGAAUGAGGCAGGGGUGCUCAUGCAGAAGGCAUCUUUAGUGAUCCAAGAUUACUGGUGGUCUGUGGACAGACUGGCAACCUGCUCAGCCUCCUGUGGUAACCGGGGGGUUCAGCAGCCCCGCUUGAGGUGCCUGCUGAACAGCACGGAGGUCAACCCUGCCCACUGCGCAGGGAAGGUUCGCCCUGCGGUGCAGCCCAUCGCGUGCAACCGGAGAGACUGCCCUUCUCGGUGGAUGGUGACCUCCUGGUCUGCCUGUACCCGGAGCUGUGGGGGAGGUGUCCAGACCCGCAGGGUGACCUGUCAAAAGCUGAAAGCCUCUGGGAUCUCCACCCCUGUGUCCAAUGACAUGUGCACCCAGGUCGCCAAGCGGCCUGUGGACACCCAGGCCUGUAACCAGCAGCUGUGUGUGGAGUGGGCCUUCUCCAGCUGGGGCCAGUGCAAUGGGCCUUGCAUCGGGCCUCACCUAGCUGUGCAACACAGACAAGUCUUCUGCCAGACACGGGAUGGCAUCACCUUACCAUCAGAGCAGUGCAGUGCUCUUCCGAGGCCUGUGAGCACCCAGAACUGCUGGUCAGAGGCCUGCAGUGUACACUGGAGAGUCAGCCUGUGGACCCUGUGCACAGCUACCUGUGGCAACUACGGCUUCCAGUCCCGGCGUGUGGAGUGUGUGCAUGCCCGCACCAACAAGGCAGUGCCUGAGCACCUGUGCUCCUGGGGGCCCCGGCCUGCCAACUGGCAGCGCUGCAACAUCACCCCAUGUGAAAACAUGGAGUGCAGAGACACCACCAGGUACUGCGAGAAGGUGAAACAGCUGAAACUCUGCCAACUCAGCCAGUUUAAAUCUCGCUGCUGUGGAACUUGUGGCAAAGCGUGAAGAUAGGGUGUGGGGAAAAACUCUACCCUGGCCACACGAAGGACUCACGCAACCACCUCGGACAGAACCUAAGCUUUCUUCAUUUUAUUUAUUUAUUUCCCCCUCCCCACUCCACACACACCCUUCCAACCUCCUCCACCUCCACCUUCAAGCAUAAGGACGUCCGCGUGUUUUCUCUUUCAGUUAGCUGGAGGACAGGAUGUUGGGAAAGGAAAGGACAGAUGUCUAAAGGAGGUUGCAGAGCAGGCCAGGCAGACAGUGGGGGCUCCCUUGAAGAGCUUCCUCCCUCCCAAACCUGGGUCUCAAAGACCUAGAAAGAGGCAGGCACAGCCCCUGCGGACAGCAGGGAGCCAGAAGGUUUGUAGCCUAUUGGUGCAAACAUUGGACAAAUUCCUGUGUCUUUCCUAGAAGCGCACUAUCACAAACACAGGAGUGUUUUGCUCCUUUGUCUCCUCUUCCCCAUCUAUGUCCCUUUAGUCACAGUUAGGACAAAUGGGGAGGGGACACCAUGCUGAGGCAGAAACUAGCCCAGAACUCACUCAGUUCUUCUAGUGGGUGAGUGCAGAGAGAGAAGAACUCAGAUCACCAGUAGGGAGAGGUAAAAAAGCAAACAAAGCAGGCUCUAAGGCACACAACAUUGCAGAAAAUGAGGAAGGGAGGGGAGGGAAGGGACAGAAGCAAAAAGGAGCCUGUGGUGUUCCCCAGUGGGGCAGGGUGAGCAGGGGCUUCCAGGCUGCAUGAGGCUCAUGGACCAGCUCUGAUCCCAUGCAUGUGCGCAUGCUCAGAGCCCUGCUGCCCACAACAGAGCACUGCGCUGCGUGGGAGUCCCCACUUCCCAAGCUAUCAGAGUCAACGUCCUGCCUGUGCAGCUGCAGCAAAGCCAGUGAGAGGUGGGUCUCGCCAUGCAGUAAGGCCACCCUGGCACCUCUUUAUCUAAAUCCGAAGUCCCCUAGCCCCGCACUAACUAACUGCUGCUGUGGGCCAGGGCCAUUUUGAGCAUGAAUGGCCCAGGUUUUUUGCCUUCUAGGACCUUUGCUGCUCCACCGAAGGGCCAGGGACUAUGGUUAACUUAUCAACAUCAACCCAUUAACUAGUCACUGUGCCAGAGAGUAUCUGUCAGGCUGUCAGGUUGUAGCAACCUCUUCAUUCCAGAGCUGGCCCAGGGACCGGGGUGGGACAAUGGGUUUAUGCGUGUCCACAGUACACCCUCCCUCUCCCAGCCUCCACCCCAGGGUCUGCAGGUCCUCCGGCAUGUAGUAUUUAUCUAGCAAGGCGGGGUGGUGGAGGCAGCACCCUGGCAAAGCAGCUCACACACUGCAGCCACACUCAUCAGCUGUGGUGAGGCGGCUGGAGCAAAGUCAAAGUCAUGCAGCAAAAUGAAAACUCUGGGACUCUUCGGCAAAAUCCUCAUUAAGCCGAGCAGCUUUGGCCAAGUAAUUUUUGCCUCCUUCCCUCGCGUGGCCUGAGUUUAGGAGCAAGGGUGGCCAGAGUCCCUUACCCACAGAUAAGCCUCCCCUCAUGAAAUGCCACUCACCCCGGGCUACCAUUGACAUCAGGGCUGCAUUUCCAGCCAGCCUGGAAGUAAAAUUUGAGAGGAAGACAAUAUUAAUCUGUGUCCCCACCUAGUGAGCUGUGGACAGGUUUAAGUUGGGUCUCCUUCUUCUUCACCACAAAAACAGGCUCUAAGAAAUCAUGUUACUAAAAAAUCAGUGUAAAGUCUGUUUAAAAUAAAAAAGAAUGUUUUCUAUGUCUGUAUAUCUUUUGUGAAUAUUUAUUAGGAUUUCUUAUUAAAAAAGUGCAAUAUUAAUAAUUGUACAUUGUCAUCCAGAAACAAAACUAUUGGGGGGACUUUAUUAACUAACUUCCUGCAGUUGUGUUCCUGUAAACUCAGUAGUGAUUAUUAUAUUUUUCCUAUUUUUAAUAGAACCUGGUGUUUAACUCUGGAUCCAUUCACUGUACAGGAUGUGUUGUAAAAACUAACAUGGGAUGCUGAGGCAGUAAGAGGGAAUUCAUUUGUGGCAUAAUAGUUAUGCAUGGAAUGAUAAAGACAGACAAAUUCCAUACUACUACUAAUGUGGUUAAUUAUUUCUAGUUCGAUAGUGAUUGAAAAUCAGUGGUCACUAUUUACAUUUCCUAAAGAGCAAGCAUCCUCCAGCUCCAUGUUGGGUUGGAGCAGUUGGCAGUGGGUCUCAGUGAGCUGGCAGAACCUAGGUUUGGGUGGGAAGCAGAAUGCUCGUUGCAUGAAAUGAAUGUACAUUUAAUGUUUGUUCUGUGAAUUGCAACUCAGCAGCACCACAAGACAAUGAAGGCUGCUGGCUAAUGUGGAAGGAGGCACUUUCUCCUCUAAAACACAAAACUGUAUUUGUAUUUUUUGUACAGAUAAUACAGCUUAUUUAUUUAAA